AGUCGGAGGGAGAACACCAGGCGCGGCGCGGGCGGCUCCGGCUCCGGCCCCGGCCCAGGCCCGGGAGAGGCGAUGGCGAGCCGCGAUAGCAACCACGCUGGCGAGAGCUUUCUCGGCUCCGACGGGGACGAGGAGGCGACCCGGGAGCUGGAGACCGAGGAGGAGUCGGAGGGCGAGGAGGACGAGACGGCGGCGGAGUCGGAGGAGGAGCCGGACUCCAGGUUAUCAGACCAGGAUGAAGAGGGAAAGAUCAAGCAGGAGUAUAUCAUAUCUGACCCCUCCUUUUCCAUGGUGACAGUCCAAAGGGAAGAUAGUGGGAUAACCUGGGAAACCAAUUCAAGUAGAUCUUCUACUCCUUGGGCUUCAGAAGAAAGUCAGACUUCUGGUGUGUGUAGUCGGGAAGGGUCAACUGUGAAUUCUCCUCCUGGAAAUGUUUCCUUUAUUGUGGAUGAAGUGAAAAAGGUUCGGAAAAGGACUCAUAAGUCAAAGCAUGGUUCACCAUCAUUACGCCGGAAAGGCAACAGAAAAAGAAAUUCUUUUGAAUCCCAAGAUGUUCCAACAAACAAAAAAGGCAGUCCUUUAACUUCAGCAAGCCAGGUACUAACCACGGAGAAAGAGAAGUCAUAUACUGGCAUUUAUGAUAAAGCAAGAAAAAAGAAGACCACUUCAAAUACACCUCCGAUUACUGGGGCAAUAUACAAAGAACACAAGCCAUUAGUGUUAAGACCAGUCUACAUAGGAACAGUACAAUAUAAAAUUAAGAUGUUUAAUUCGGUUAAAGAAGAAUUAAUUCCUCUACAAUUUUAUGGAACAUUGCCAAAGGGUUAUGUAAUUAAAGAAAUACAUUAUAGGAAAGGGAAAGAUGCAUCCAUUAGUCUAGAGCCAGAUUUGGACAAUAGUGGUUCUAAUACAGUGUCCAAAACACGCAAAUUAGUAGCCCAAAGCAUAGAGGAUAAAGUAAAAGAGGUUUUUCCACCCUGGAGAGGCGCACUCUCCAAAGGAUCAGAGUCCCUAACCUUAAUGUUCAGUCAUGAAGAUCAAAAGAAAAUUUAUGCUGAUUCUCCCCUAAAUGCCACAUCUGCAUUGGAGCACACAGUUCCCUCUUAUUCAAGUAGUGGCAGAGCAGAACAAGGAAUACAGCUCAGGCAUUCACAGUCAGUGCCACAACAGCCAGAAGAUGAAGCAAAACCACAUGAAGUGGAACCUCCAUCUGUGACACCCGACACACCUGCAACUAUGUUCCUGAGAACAACAAAGGAAGAAUGUGAGCUUGCUUCACCAGGAACUGCAGCUUCAGAGAAUGACUCUUCAGUCUCACCAUCAUUUGCUAAUGAGGUAAAGAAGGAAGAUGUGUAUUCUGCUCACCAUUCCAUUUCUCUGGAGGCAGCGUCACCAGGUCUGGCAGCAUCUACCCAGGAUGGUUUGGACCCAGACCAAGAACAGCCGGACCUGACUUCAAUAGAAAGGGCAGAACCAGUCUCCGCAAAACUGACCCCUACCCAUCCCAGUGUCAAAGGAGAGAAGGAGGAAAACAUGCUUGAGCCAUCCAUUUCUCUUUCUGAACCUCUAAUGUUAGAAGAACCAGAGAAAGAAGAAAUAGAAACUUCCCUACCCAUAGCUAUUACCCCUGAACCUGAAGAUUCUAAUUUAGUAGAAGAAGAGAUCGUAGAACUUGAUUACCCAGAAAGCCCAUUGGUUUCCGAGAAGCCCUUCCCACCACAUAUGUCCCCUGAAGUGGAGCACAAAGAAGAAGAGCUUAUUCUACCAUUAUUGGCAGCAUCAUCUCCUGAACAUGUUGCUUUGUCUGAGGAAGAAAGAGAGGAAAUUGCAUCUGUUUCUACUGGUUCUGCUUUUGUAUCAGAGUAUUCAGUACCACAGGAUUUGAACCAUGAAUUACAGGAGCAAGAAGGUGAGCCAGUUCCCCCAUCCAAUGUAGAAGCUAUAGCUGAACAUGCAGUUUUGUCAGAAGAAGAGAAUGAGGAAUUUGAGGCUUAUUCCCCAGCUGCAGCCCCUACAUCUGAGAGCUCUCUCUCACCAUCCACAACUGAGAAGACUUCAGAGAACCAGUCUCCACUGUUUUCAACAGUUACACCAGAAUACAUGGUCCUAUCAGGAGACGAGGCCUCAGAAAGUGGGUGUUACACACCAGACUCCACAUCUGCUUCUGAAUAUUCAGUUCCAUCACUGGCAACAAAAGAGUCACUGAAGAAAACAAUUGACCGUAAGUCCCCGUUAAUAUUGAAAGGUGUUUCUGAGUACAUGAUUCCAUCAGAAGAGAAGGAAGACACUGGAUCGUUUACUCCAGCUGUGGCCCCUGCUUCUGAGCCCUCUCUCUCACCAUCCACAACCGAAAAGACUUCUGAAUGCCAGUCACCACUGCCUUCUACUGCCACAUCAGAACACGUGGUCCCAUCAGAAGGAGAGGACCUAGGAAGUGAACGUUUCACACCGGAUUCAAAGUUGAUCUCCAAAUAUGCAGCCCCACUCAAUGCAACACAGGAAUCUCAAAAGAAAAUAAUCAAUGAGGCAUCCCAAUUCAAACCAAAAGGUAUUUCUGAGCACACAGUUCUGUCAGUAGACGGCAAGGAGGUCAUUGGACCAUCUUCCCCAGAUUUGGUUGUUGCAUCUGAACACUCUUUCCCACCACACACAACCGAGAUGACUUCUGAAUGCCAGGCCCCACCACUUUCAGCCACCCCAUCUGAAUAUGUUGUUCUAUCAGACGAAGAGGCAGUCGAGUUGGAACGAUACACACCCUCUUCUACAUCUGCUUCUGAAUUUUCAGUACCACCAUAUGCAACACCGGAGGCACAGGAGGAAGAAAUUGUCCAUAGAUCUCUAAAUCUAAAAGGUGCAUCCUCACCCAUGAAUUUAUCAGAAGAAGAUCAAGAAGACAUUGGACCUUUUUCUCCAGAUUCUGCAUUUGUGUCAGAAUUCUCAUUUCCACCGUAUGCAACCCAGGAAGCAGAGAAAAGAGAAUUUGAGUGCGAUUCUCCAAUAUGUUUAACAUCACCAUCUGAGCACACUAUUUUGUCAGAUGAAGACACUGAAGAAGCGGAACUGUUCUCUCCAGACUCAGCAUCACAAGUUUCAAUCCCUCCCUUUAGAAUCUCAGAAACAGAGAAAAAUGAACUUGAGCCUGAUUCACUAUUAACUGCAGUGUCUGCUUCAGGUUAUUCCUGCUUUUCAGAAGCAGAUGAGGAAGACAUUGGAUCCACAGCUGCUACACCUGUAUCUGAGCAGUUCAGUUCAUCACAGAAGCAAAAAGCUGAAACUUUCCCUUUGAUGUCUCCGCUUGAAGACUUAAGUCUGCCGCCUUCAACAGAUAAAUCAGAGAAAGCAGAAAUUAAGCCAGAGAUUCCAACAACCUCAACAUCUGUAUCUGAAUAUCUCAUUUUGGCACAGAAGCAGAAAACUCAAGCAUAUUUAGAGCCUGAGUCUGAAGACUUGAUUCCUUCACAUUUAACCAGUGAAGUGGAGAAGGGAGAAAGGGAGGCAAGUUCAUCAGUAGCUGCAAUACCUGCUGCUUUACCUGCACAAUCAUCUAUAGUAAAGGAAGAAACCAAACCUGCAUCUCCACAUUCAGUUUUACCUGAUUCAGUCCCUGCAAUCAAGAAAGAACAGGAACCCACAGCAGCACUCACUCUAAAAGCUGCAGAUGAACAGAUGGCUUUGUCAAAAGUCAGAAAGGAAGAAAUUGUGCCUGAUUCUCAAGAAGCUACAGCACAUGUAUCACAGGAUCAAAAAAUGGAGCCUCAGCCUCCAAAUGUUCCAGAGUCUGAGAUGAAAUAUUCAGUUUUGCCUGACAUGGUAGAUGAGCCAAAGAAGGGUGUCAAGCCCAAAUUAGUUCUAAAUGUGACUUCUGAACUAGAACAGAGAAAGUUGUCCAAGAAUGAGCCUGAAGUAAUAAAACCAUAUUCACCUCUAAAGGAAACAUCUUUAUCUGGACCUGAGGCUUUAUCAGCAGUGAAAAUGGAGAUGAAACAUGAUUCCAAAAUAACAACUACACCUAUAGUGCUUCAUUCAGCUUCCUCAGGAGUGGAAAAGCAAGUUGAACAUGGUCCACCUGCACUAGCAUUUUCAGCUUUGUCAGAAGAAAUUAAAAAAGAAAUUGAACCCAGUUCCUCAACAACUACAGCAUCUGUAACUAAGCUUGAUUCAAACUUAACCAGAGCAGUAAAAGAAGAAAUCCCAACAGAUUCAUCUCUUAUCACUCCUGUAGAUCGUCCAGUCUUAACAAAAGUAGGAAAGGGUGAAUUAGGAAGUGGUUUGCCACCACUGGUAACAUCUGCAGAUGAACAUUCAGUUCUUGCAGAAGAAGACAAGGUGGCAAUUAAAGGUGCUUCUCCCAUUGAAACUUCAUCCAAACAUUUAGCUUGGUCAGAAGCAGAGAAGGAAAUUAAAUUUGAUUCACUUCCAAGUGUCUCCUCUAUAGCAGAGCAUUCUGUUUUGUCAGAAGUAGAAGCCAAAGAAGUUAAAGCUGGGUUGCCAGUAAUCAAAACAUCAUCUUCUCAGCAUUCAGAUAAAUCUGAGGAAGCAAGGGUAGAAGACAAACAAGAUCUUUUAUUUUCUACAGUCUGUGACUCUGAACGUUUGGUUUCAUCACAGAAGAAGAGCUUGAUGUCUACCUCAGAGGUGUUAGAGCCUGAACAUGAGCUUCCACUCAGCCUAUGGGGUGAGAUAAAGAAGAAAGAAACUGAACUUCCUUCAUCACAAAAUGUGUCACCUGCAUCCAAACAUAUAAUCCCAAAAGGCAAAGAUGAGGAAACAGCAAGUUCAUCUCCUGAGUUGGAAAAUUUAGCAUCAGGUUUAGCCCCAACAUUACUGCUCCUCAGUGAUGAUAAGAACAAACCGGCAGUGGAGGUAUCUUCUACAGCUCAGGGAGACUUCCCAUCAGAAAAACAAGAUGUUGCUUUGGCAGAGCUGUCUUUGGAACCUGAGAAGAAAGACAAGCCACACCAACCGUUGGAAUUACCAAAUGCUGGGUCAGAAUUUUCUAGUGAUUUAGGUAGACAAAGUGGAUCCAUAGGUACAAAACAAGCAAAGUCUCCCAUAACUGAAACAGAGGAUUCUGUUUUAGAAAAAGGCCCAGCUGAGCUUAGGAGCAGAGAAGGAAAAGAAGAAAAUAGAGAGCUUUGUGCAUCUUCUACGAUGCCUGCAAUUUCAGAGCUUUCAUCAUUGCUUAGGGAGGAAUCUCAGAAUGAAGAAAUUAAACCUUUCUCUCCCAAGAUCAUCAGCCUAGAGUCGAAAGAACCACCUGCCUCUGUAGCUGAAGGAGGCAACCCAGAAGAAUUUCAGCCAUUUACUUUUUCUUUAAAAGGAUUAUCAGAGGAGGUUAGCCAUCCAGCCGACUUUAAAAAGGGAGGAAAUCAAGAAAUAGGCCCAUUACCACCAACUGGAAAUUUGAAGGCACAAGUCAUGGGAGAUAUUUUAGAUAAGCUAAGUGAAGAAACAGGCCACCCAAAUUCAUCCCAGGUACUCCAGAGUAUAACAGAACCAUCAAAGAUUGCUCCUUCUGACCUCCUUGUAGAACAAAAAAAGACAGAAAAAGCACUUCAUUCAGAUCAAACUGUUAAAUUACCUGAUGUAAGCACCUCUUCUGAAGAUAAACAAGAUCUGGGUAUUAAGCAGUUUUCACUUAUGAGAGAGAAUUUGCCUUUGGAACAAUCAAAAUCAUUUAUGACAACCAAGCCUGCGGAUGUCAAAGAAACAAAAAUGGAAGAAUUCUUUAUUUCUCCAAAGGAUGAAAACUGGAUGUUGGGAAAGCCAGAAAAUGUGGCUAGUCAACACGAACAGAGAAUAGCAGGAUCUGUGCAGCUGGAUUCCUCUAGCAGCAAUGAGCUGAGGCCAGGGCAGCUCAAGGCUGCUGUGUCCAGUAAGGACCAUACAUGUGAAGUGAGAAAGCAGGUCCUGCCGCAUUCUGCUGAAGAAUCUCAUUUGUCAUCACAAGAAGCAGUAUCUGCUCUUGAUACUUCCAGUGGUAAUACAGAGACCUUAUCAAGUAAAAGUUACUCUUCUGAAGAAGUAAAGCUGGCUGAAGAACCAAAGUCUUUAGUCCUAGCUGGAAAUGUAGAGAGAAACAUAGCAGAGGGGAAGGAGAUUCAUUCUUUGAUGGAGAGUGAAAGUUUGCUAUUGGAGAAAGCAAACACAGAGCUUUCCUGGCCUUCCAAAGAAGAUAGCCAGGAAAAAAUUAAACUACCUCCUGAAAGAUUCUUCCAGAAACCAGUGUCUGGCCUAUCAGUGGAACAGGUGAAGUCAGAAACAAUCUCCUCUUCUGUCAAAACAGCCCAUUUCCCGGCAGAAGGUGUGGAACCUGCAUUGGGCAAUGAAAAAGAAGCACACAGGAGCACACCUCCUUUUCCUGAAGAGAAGCCAUUGGAAGAAUCAAAAAUGGUUCAGUCAAAGGUUAUUGAUGAUGCUGAUGAGGGAAAGAAACCAUCACCUGAAGUAAAAAUACCCACACAAAGAAAACCCAUCUCCUCAAUCCAUGCAAGAGAGCCUCAAUCCCCAGAGUCACCUGAGGUGACACAAAAUCCACCUACACAACCAAAGGUGGCUAAGCCGGACCUUCCUGAGGAAAAGGGAAAGAAAGGAAUUUCAUCUUUCAAAUCGUGGAUGUCCAGCUUGUUUUUUGGAUCGAGCACUCCAGAUAACAAAGUUGCUGAACAAGAAGACUUAGAAACACAGCCAAGUCCAUCCGUAGAAAAAGCAGUGACUGUGAUAGAUCCUGAAGGUACAAUUCCCACCAAUUUUAAUGUAGCUGAGAAACCAGCUGAUCAUUCAUUAUCAGAGGUAAAACUUAAAACUGCUGAUGAACCCAGAGGUACUUUAGUAAAAUCUGGUGACGGUCAAAACGUUAAAGAAAAAUCCAUGAUUUUAUCAAAUGUAGAAGAUUUACAACAGCCAAAAUUCAUUUCUGAGGUGUCUAGGGAAGAUUAUGGAAAAAAAGAAAUCUCAGGCGAUUCAGAGGAAAUGAACAUAAACUCAGUAGUUACUUCUGCUGAUGGUGAGAACCUUGAAAUUCAAUCUUAUUCACUAAUCGGUGAGAAAUUGGUUAUGGAAGAAGCCAAAACUAUUGUUCCUCCUCAUGUUACUGAUAGUAAAAGAGUCCAGAAGCCAGCAAUCGCUCCUCCAUCUAAAUGGAAUAUUUCUAUUUUUAAGGAAGAGCCAAGAAGUGAUCAAAAACAAAAAUCACUCCUUUCAUUUGAUGUAGUAGAUAAGGUGCCACAACAGCCAAAAUCAGCUUCCUCCAACUUUGCAAGUAAAAAUAUCACAAAGGAAUCAGAGAAACCAGAGUCAAUUAUUUUGCCAGUAGAAGAAUCAAAAGGCAGUUUAAUUGAUUUCAGUGAAGACAGACUCAAGAAAGAAAUGCAAAAUCCUACUUCCUUGAAAAUUUCUGAAGAGGAAACAAAACUCAGGUCUGUUAGUCCAACUGAGAAGAAAGAUAAUUUGGAAAACAGAUCAUAUACCUUGGCAGAAAAGAAGGUGCUGGCAGAAAAACAAAACUCUGUGGCCCCAUUAGAGCUUAGAGAUAGUAAUGAAAUAGGGAAGACACAAAUUACACUUGGAUCUAGAUCUACUGAACUGAAAGAAUCAAAAGCCGAUGCUAUGCCACAGCACUUCUAUCAAAAUGAAGACUACAAUGAAAGACCCAAAAUCAUUGUUGGUUCUGAAAAGGAGAAAGGUGAAGAAAAAGAAAAUCAGGUAUAUGUGCUUUCAGAAGGAAAGAAGCAGCAGGAACAUCAGCCUUAUUCUGUGAAUGUAGCCGAGUCUAUGAGUAGAGAAUCAGAUAUCUCUUUAGGUCAUUCUUUGGGUGAAACUCAAUCAUUUUCAUUAGUUAAAGCUACAUCAGUUACUGAAAAAUCAGAAGCCAUGCUCGCAGAGGCUCACCCAGAAAUCAGAGAAGCAAAGGCAGUAGGAACCCAACCACAUCCUUUAGAAGAAAGUAAAGUUUUGGUGGAGAAAACCAAGACUUUCCUGCCGGUGGCUCUUUCUUGUCGUGAUGAAAUAGAGAACCACUCUUUAUCUCAGGAAGGAAAUCUAGUAUUAGAAAAGUCAAGCAGAGAUAUGCCAGAUCACAGUGAAGAAAAAGAACAGUUCAGAGAGUCAGAGCUAUCGAAAGGCGGUUCAGUAGAUAUCACAAAAGAAACUGUGAAACAAGGAUUUCAAGAAAAGGCAGUAGGAACCCAACCACGUCCUUUAGAAGAAAGUAAAGUUUUGGUGGAGAAAACUAAGACUUUCCUGCCAGUGGUUCUUUCUUGUCAUGAUGAAAUAGAGAACCACUCUUUGUCUCAGGAAGGAAAUCUAGUGUUAGAAAAGUCAAGCAGAGAUAUGCCAGAUCACAGUGAAGAAAAAGAACAGUUCAAAGAGUCAGAGCUAUGGAAAGGUGGUUCAGUAGAUAUCACAAAAGAAAGUAUGAAAGAAGGAUUUCCAUCUAAAGAAUCCGAAAGGACUUUAGCUCGUCCUUUUGAUGAAACUAAGAGCUCAGAAACACCGCCAUAUUUGCUGUCACCUGUAAAACCACAAACUCUUGCUUCAGGAGCUUCUCCAGAAAUUAACGCAGUGAAGAAAAAAGAAAUGCCACGAUCAGAAUUGACUCCAGAAAGGCAUACAGUUCAUACUAUUCAGACAUCUAAAGAUGACACAUCCGAUGUGCCUAAACAAUCUGUUCUUGUUUCAAAGCACCACUUGGAGGCUGCGGAAGAUACCCGUGUAAAGGAACCACUGUCUUCAGCAAAAAGCAACUAUGCUCAAUUUAUAUCUAAUACAUCAGCAAGCAAUGCUGAUAAAAUGGUUUCUAAUAAAGAAAUGCCCAAGGAACCUGAAGACACAUAUGCAAAAGGUGAAGACUUUACAGUGACUAGUAAGCCAGCCGGACUUUCAGAAGAUCAGAAGACUGCCUUUAGUAUCAUUUCUGAAGGCUGUGAGAUAUUGAAUAUUCAUGCUCCGGCCUUUAUUUCUUCAAUCGAUCAGGAAGAAAGUGAACAAAUGCAAGAUAAAUUAGAAUAUUUGGAAGAGAAAGCCUCAUUUAAAACCAUACCACUCCCUGAUGAUAGUGAAACAGUUGCUUGUCAUAAAACAUUAAAGAGCAGGUUAGAAGAUGAAAAAGUUACCCCAUUGAAAGAAAAUAAACAAAAGGAAACUCAUAAGACAAAAGAAGAGAUAUCCACAGAUUCAGAAACUGAUUUAUCAUUUAUUCAGCCCACAAUUCCCAGUGAAGAGGAUUAUUUUGAAAAAUAUACUUUGAUUGAUUAUAACAUCUCCCCAGACCCAGAAAAACAGAAAGCUCCACAGAAAUUAAAUGUUGAAGAGAAACUCUCAAAGGAAGUUACAGAAGAAACUAUCUCUUUCCCAGUAAGUUCAGUGGAAAGUGCACUAGAACAUGAAUAUGACUUGGUGAAAUUAGAUGAAAGUUUUUAUGGACCAGAAAAGGGCCACAACAUAUUAUCUCAUCCAGAGACCCAAAGCCAAAACUCAGCUGACAGGAAUGUUUCAAAGGACACAAAGAGAGAUGUGGACUCAAAGUCACCGGGGAUGCCUUUAUUUGAAGCAGAGGAAGGAGUUCUAUCACGAACCCAGAUAUUUCCUACCACUAUUAAAGUCAUUGAUCCAGAAUUUCUGGAGGAGCCACCUGCACUUGCAUUUUUAUAUAAGGAUCUGUAUGAAGAAGCAGUUGGAGAGAAAAAGAAGGAAGAGGAGACAGCUUCUGAAGGUGACAGUGUGAAUUCUGAGGCAUCAUUUCCCAGCAGAAAUUCUGACACUGAUGAUGGAACAGGAAUAUAUUUUGAGAAGUACAUACUCAAAGAUGACAUUCUCCAUGACACAUCUCUAACUCAAAAGGACCAGGGCCAAGGUCUGGAAGAAAAACGAGUUGGUAAGGAUGAUUCAUACCAACCGAUAGCUGCAGAAGGGGAAAUUUGGGGAAAGUUUGGAACUAUUUGCAGGGAGAAGAGUCUGGAAGAACAGAAAGGUGUUUAUGGGGAAGGAGAAUCAGUAGACCAUGUGGAGACCGUUGGUAACGUAGCGAUGCAGAAGAAAGCUCCCAUCACAGAGGACGUCAGAGUGGCUACCCAGAAAAUAAGUUAUGCGGUUCCAUUUGAAGACACCCAUCAUGUUCUGGAGCGUGCAGAUGAAGCAGGCAGUCACGGUAAUGAAGUCGGAAAUGCAAGUCCAGAGGUCAAUCUGAAUGUCCCAGUACAAGUGUCCUUCCCGGAGGAAGAAUUUGCAUCUGGUGCAACUCAUGUUCAAGAAACAUCACUAGAAGAACCUAAAAUCCUGGUCCCACCUGAGCCAAGUGAAGAGAGGCUCCGUAAUAGCCCUGUUCAGGAUGAGUAUGAAUUUACAGAAUCCCUGCAUAAUGAAGUGGUUCCUCAAGACAUAUUAUCAGAAGAACUGUCUUCAGAAUCCACACCUGAAGAUGUCUUAUCUCAAGGAAAGGAAUCCUUUGAGCACAUCAGUGAAAAUGAAUUUGCGAGUGAGGCAGAACAAAGUACACCUGCUGAACAAAAAGAGUUGGGCAGCGAGAGGAAAGAAGAAGACCAAUUAUCAUCUGAGGUAGUAACUGAAAAGGCACAAAAAGAGCUGAAAAAGUCCCAGAUUGACACAUACUGUUACACCUGCAAAUGUCCAAUUUCUGCCACUGACAAGGUGUUUGGCACCCACAAAGACCAUGAAGUUUCAACGCUUGACACAGCUAUAAGUGCUGUAAAGGUUCAAUUAGCAGAAUUUCUAGAAAAUUUACAAGAAAAGUCCUUGAGGAUUGAAGCCUUUGUUAGUGAGAUAGAAUCCUUUUUUAAUACCAUUGAGGAAAACUGUAGUAAAAAUGAGAAAAGGCUAGAAGAACAGAAUGAGGAAAUGAUGAAGAAGGUUUUAGCACAGUAUGAUGAGAAAGCCCAGAGCUUUGAGGAAGUGAAGAAGAAGAAGAUGGAGUUCCUGCAUGAGCAGAUGGUCCACUUUCUGCAGAGCAUGGACACUGCCAAAGACACCCUGGAGACCAUCGUGAGAGAAGCAGAGGAGCUUGAUGAGGCCGUCUUCCUGACUUCGUUUGAGGAAAUCAAUGAAAGGUUGCUUUCUGCAAUGGAGAGCACUGCUUCUUUAGAGAAAAUGCCUGCUGCGUUUUCCCUUUUCGAACAUUAUGAUGACAGCUCGGCAAGAAGUGACCAGAUGUUAAAACAAGUGGCUGUUCCACAGCCUCCUAGAUUAGAACCUCAGGAACCAAAUUCUGCCACCAGCACAACAAUUGCAGUUUACUGGAGCAUGAACAAGGAAGAUGUCAUUGAUUCAUUUCAGGUUUACUGCAUGGAGGAGCCACAAGAUGAUCAAGAAGUAAAUGAGUUGGUAGAAGAAUACAGACUGACAGUGAAAGAAAGCUACUGCAUUUUUGAAGAUCUGGAACCUGACCGAUGCUAUCAAGUGUGGGUGAUGGCUGUGAACUUCACUGGAUGUAGCCUGCCCAGUGAAAGGGCCAUCUUUAGGACAGCACCCUCCACCCCUGUGAUCCGCGCUGAGGACUGUACUGUGUGUUGGAACACAGCCACUAUCCGAUGGCGGCCCACCACCCCAGAGGCCACGGAGACCUACACUCUGGAGUACUGCAGACAGCACUCUCCUGAGGGAGAGGGCCUCAGAUCUUUCUCUGGAAUCAAAGGACUCCAGCUGAAAGUUAACCUCCAACCCAAUGAUAACUACUUUUUCUAUGUGAGGGCCAUCAAUGCAUUUGGGACAAGUGAACAGAGUGAAGCUGCUCUCAUCUCCACCAGAGGAACCAGAUUUCUCUUGUUGAGAGAAACAGCUCAUCCUGCUCUACACAUUUCCUCAAGUGGGACAGUGAUCAGCUUUGGUGAGAGGAGACGGCUGACGGAAAUCCCGUCAGUGCUGGGUGAGGAGCUGCCUUCCUGUGGCCAGCAUUACUGGGAAACCACAGUCACAGACUGCCCAGCAUAUCGACUCGGCAUCUGCUCCAGCUCGGCUGUGCAGGCAGGUGCCCUAGGACAAGGGGAGACCUCAUGGUACAUGCACUGCUCUGAGCCACAGAGAUACACAUUUUUCUACAGUGGUAUUGUGAGUGAUGUUCAUGUGACUGAGCGUCCAGCCAGAGUGGGCAUCCUGCUGGACUACAACAACCAGAGACUUAUCUUCAUCAACGCAGAGAGCGAGCAGUUGCUCUUCAUCAUCAGGCACAGGUUUAAUGAGGGUGUCCACCCUGCCUUUGCCCUGGAGAAACCUGGAAAAUGUACUUUGCACCUGGGGAUAGAGCCCCCGGAUUCUGUAAGGCACAAGUGAUCCUUGGCUUUCAGAAUUUGCAAGAACAGCGAUUUGAAUUUUGGGGGGGUCUGCUGUUCAUUCCUUUAGGUGCUAUACAUUAUUCAAAAAGUCUCCCGCGCAUUUGCACUAAUGAUGGCUGCAUGCAUAGCAAUCAGCAUGUGAGCAAAAUCGACAAGAAAACCUUGACUUUACAGAGCAGUGUGUGAGUAAACAGAAUGAAAACAACAACCUCCACUCUUUAGUUUAUAUAAGUUUGAGUUCUUUCCUAAAUUAAAAGAUCUACACUUGAGUUGGGAACCGAAAGAGAAAAAUGGACUUCCAUCUGUUUUACUGGUAAAGGAAAUCCUCUGAUGGACAGGUCAGAGUGAAGGAAGGUUGUGCUGGUAAGACAUCUCUGACGAAGAGCCAUGGAUGCUUUCCACAAAAUGUCACCUCGCUGCACUAAAGGAUGAUGAAUCCUAAUCAUUAAAGGAAUUGUUUCAGCUGAUUUAAAUUUAUAAUGAACUCUUUUGUAAUAAUGUAUACUGUAGAACAUGAGUCUCUCCUCCCUAAAAUUUUAAAUGUAGAAAAGUGCUAUAUAUUAGAAAUUUCCAUUUUGUUAAAUAAAUGGUUAGAGUCUAUAAA